GCCAGUUCUCUUCGGGGACUAACUGCAACGGAGAGACUCAAGAUGAUUCCCUUUUUACCCAUGUUUUCUCUACUAUUGCUGCUUAUUGUUAACCCUAUAAACGCCAACAAUCAUUAUGACAAGAUCUUGGCUCAUAGUCGUAUCAGGGGUCGGGACCAAGGCCCAAAUGUCUGUGCCCUUCAACAGAUUUUGGGCACCAAAAAGAAAUACUUCAGCACUUGUAAGAACUGGUAUAAAAAGUCCAUCUGUGGACAGAAAACGACUGUGUUAUAUGAAUGUUGCCCUGGUUAUAUGAGAAUGGAAGGAAUGAAAGGCUGCCCAGCAGUUUUGCCCAUUGACCAUGUUUAUGGCACUCUGGGCAUCGUGGGAGCCACCACAACGCAGCGCUAUUCUGACGCCUCAAAACUGAGGGAGGAGAUCGAGGGAAAGGGAUCCUUCACUUACUUUGCACCGAGUAAUGAGGCUUGGGACAACUUGGAUUCUGAUAUCCGUAGAGGUUUGGAGAGCAACGUGAAUGUUGAAUUACUGAAUGCUUUACAUAGUCACAUGAUUAAUAAGAGAAUGUUGACCAAGGACUUAAAAAAUGGCAUGAUUAUUCCUUCAAUGUAUAACAAUUUGGGGCUUUUCAUUAACCAUUAUCCUAAUGGGGUUGUCACUGUUAAUUGUGCUCGAAUCAUCCAUGGGAACCAGAUUGCAACAAAUGGUGUUGUCCAUGUCAUUGACCGUGUGCUUACACAAAUUGGUACCUCAAUUCAAGACUUCAUUGAAGCAGAAGAUGACCUUUCAUCUUUUAGAGCAGCUGCCAUCACAUCGGACAUAUUGGAGGCCCUUGGAAGAGACGGUCACUUCACACUCUUUGCUCCCACCAAUGAGGCUUUUGAGAAACUUCCACGAGGUGUCCUAGAAAGGAUCAUGGGAGACAAAGUGGCUUCCGAAGCUCUUAUGAAGUACCACAUCUUAAAUACUCUCCAGUGUUCUGAGUCUAUUAUGGGAGGAGCAGUCUUUGAGACGCUGGAAGGAAAUACAAUUGAGAUAGGAUGUGACGGUGACAGUAUAACAGUAAAUGGAAUCAAAAUGGUGAACAAAAAGGAUAUUGUGACAAAUAAUGGUGUGAUCCAUUUGAUUGAUCAGGUCCUAAUUCCUGAUUCUGCCAAACAAGUUAUUGAGCUGGCUGGAAAACAGCAAACCACCUUCACGGAUCUUGUGGCCCAAUUAGGCUUGGCAUCUGCUCUGAGGCCAGAUGGAGAAUACACUUUGCUGGCACCUGUGAAUAAUGCAUUUUCUGAUGAUACUCUCAGCAUGGAUCAGCGCCUCCUUAAAUUAAUUCUGCAGAAUCACAUAUUGAAAGUAAAAGUUGGCCUUAAUGAGCUUUACAACGGGCAAAUACUGGAAACCAUCGGAGGCAAACAGCUCAGAGUCUUCGUAUAUCGUACAGCUGUCUGCAUUGAAAAUUCAUGCAUGGAGAAAGGGAGUAAGCAAGGGAGAAACGGUGCGAUUCACAUAUUCCGCGAGAUCAUCAAGCCAGCAGAGAAAUCCCUCCAUGAAAAGUUAAAACAAGAUAAGCGCUUUAGCACCUUCCUCAGCCUACUUGAAGCUGCAGACUUGAAAGAGCUCCUGACACAACCUGGAGACUGGACAUUAUUUGUGCCAACCAAUGAUGCUUUUAAGGGAAUGACUAGUGAAGAAAAAGAAAUUCUGAUACGGGACAAAAAUGCUCUUCAAAACAUCAUUCUUUAUCACCUGACACCAGGAGUUUUCAUUGGAAAAGGAUUUGAACCUGGUGUUACUAACAUUUUAAAGACCACACAAGGAAGCAAAAUCUUUCUGAAAGAAGUAAAUGAUACACUUCUGGUGAAUGAAUUGAAAUCAAAAGAAUCUGACAUCAUGACAACAAAUGGUGUAAUUCAUGUUGUAGAUAAACUCCUCUAUCCAGCAGACACACCUGUUGGAAAUGAUCAACUGCUGGAAAUACUUAAUAAAUUAAUCAAAUACAUCCAAAUUAAGUUUGUUCGUGGUAGCACCUUCAAAGAAAUCCCCGUGACUGUCUAUACAACUAAAAUUAUAACCAAAGUUGUGGAACCAAAAAUUAAAGUGAUUGAAGGCAGUCUUCAGCCUAUUAUCAAAACUGAAGGACCCACACUAACAAAAGUCAAAAUUGAAGGUGAACCUGAAUUCAGACUGAUUAAAGAAGGUGAAACAAUAACUGAAGUGAUCCAUGGAGAGCCAAUUAUUAAAAAAUACACCAAAAUCAUUGAUGGAGUGCCUGUGGAAAUAACUGAAAAAGAGACACGAGAAGAACGAAUCAUUACAGGUCCUGAAAUAAAAUACACUAGGAUUUCUACUGGAGGUGGAGAAACAGAAGAAACUCUGAAGAAAUUGUUACAAGAAGAGGUCACCAAGGUCACCAAAUUCAUUGAAGGUGGUGAUGGUCAUUUAUUUGAAGAUGAAGAAAUUAAAAGACUGCUUCAGGGAGCGAAUUGAAAACAUGUAUAUAAUAGAAAAAACUGGACUUCAUGCUGAGUAUAGAUGAUACAUAUAAAAGAAGUCAAAAUUUGGAGAAAAAAUUUAAAAAGAUAAGUAGAAAAAUGAAGUAACUGUAGAAACCAUACUUACUCUUUGAUCUCAAAUGCCCAAAAACUGAAUGAAAAUGUGAAUUUAGGCCGACCAGGUAGUCUUGUCAAUAAACUAAAAGAAAAACAGGAAAAUUGAGAAAUAUGUUACAACUAUAACAACACAAAACAGCAUAGUUUUGAAACACUUGCAGUUCUUAAAUAUAAAAGCUUUUAUUAGUUAAUUUUUUAAAAGGAUCUCAUAGGAUUGACACUGAAUCAGGUUGGGAGGUGGAACAAGGGUGAUGGCAUAUUCUUUCUGAAUUACUUAUUAUAACAUUUCUAGAAUCAUUAGGUCAGUGCUACUUUGUUGUCGUCAAUGUACAAUAAAGGAAUCACAAAUUGAUCUUAGUGAUAAUUUUACAGAGGCAGACAUUGCACAUAGGUAUGACUGCAAAAAUGGGUGGCUAACUCUGGGAAGAUACUUGUGUUAAACUUUAUAUGACAUUUAAUAACCCUUCAUCAUAAGGCAAUGUUUUUUACAAAAAGAUUGAAAAAAUCAUGUAAGUCAUUUACUCUGCAAAAAUGGCACAUUAGGUGGGGUUCCAAAAUCCAUAAUGAAACAAUGUGUUUUGCAACUAAGAAACAUUCAUUAUGAUAUAUGGAAAACACUGUCUGUCUACUUGUCCUUUACGAAAAAAUGUAAAACUCUGAGGAUCAUAAAAUUUAACUACUAAAAAUAAUCUUCGUGUUUAAGUGAUACUUAUUUAAGACUUUACACUGUUCUGUUUAACCAUGGUCUCCUGUCUGAUUUUAGCCAUAAUUGCGAAGUAUUUCUAACUACAACAAUUUAAUUUUAGACACACCCGUGAGGAAGUUGCAAGCCAA